AUGGUCCCCACCAGUCUGUUGACUUUGUGGUUCUGUUAUUUUUUUCUCACUUACCUUUGCCUUUACUACUUAUCUACAUUUUUGCGCAGCUUGCUCACUUCCGACAGAGAAAAACAAAAGGUGACAGUUCGCAUUCGGAGAAAAAGACGGCGAAGAGGAAGGGCUCGGCUGUCGAUGCGUCUGUCCAGGAGGAGAGUCCGGUAA